AUGCAGAAUAAAGCCAAAAAAACAGAAUUCUCCAAGUGUCAAGCAAAAACACAUACUUUGCACACGUUUCUCGAGGUCCAGCCCGAAAGCCUGCGCCCUGGGCGUCCCUGCUUCGGCCCCCAGAGGGGGGUGCGCUGCUCGCUCCCCUCGCUCCACCUCCCGCGUAGCCUGCGGGCCCCUGGCGGCCCAGGGCAUGGGGCAGAGACGCCAUGCCGGCUGAUACACACGCCCGGAGGAGCUUGCCCGGGUUUCCUGCUUCCUGGUCGCUCGCGCUCGCCUCCCCGCCGCCUCGCCUCCCCUCGAGCAGCCUCCGCACCCCGUUCUUUCACUCCUCGGCGCGUGAGCUCCUGGCAGCCUCACCCUUUUGCACAUGACGCGCCUCCCCGGGUCUCCCGCAGGCAGGCCUCGCUCCUCCCUCCGCCAGGCCUGCCCGGGAGGCCUCGACCCGGCGAGGUGACCCGCCCCAGGGUCGCCGGCGCGAGGACGAGGCUGGCGGUGCGCUGCUUCCUCAGAGCCGCUUCCUCAGAGCCGGCUGCGGCGGGCCCGGGCGGGAACCACGGAGCCCAGUGCACCAGCCUCCUCGGUGCUACCGCGGGACACAGAGGAAACAGGAACAGCUGGUUUCUGUGGGCAGGCCCCGGGCUGGAACUAGAGCCAGGGUGCGGCCGGCGGGGGACAGGGAAAGAGAUCACAGCGAAGACCCAGAAGAAACAAAAGGCAAGCGAAUAUUUUUAUAUCCAACUGCCUACUGGACACCAACCACGUGGACAAGUCCUGGUUGCCUCAAACUCAACAUGUUCAAAGCUGAAUACAUCACCUGCUCUCCCAAAUAUGCUCCUCUCCUGCUGUUCCCAAAAUCAGAAAAUGGCUUCACGAUCAGCUCAGUCAUCUCAAGAGCAAAUGCUGAGAGUCACCCUUGAAUCCUUCUGUUGCCUCCACAUUCAAACCAUCACCAUAUCCUUGAUUUCUCUACUGUAUAUUUUUCAUAUGUGUCCACUUCUUUCCAUCUGCACUCUCAUUAGUGAAGGCCACCAACAUCUCUCAUCUGAAUGCCUGCAAUACCUCCUCACAGGUCACCAGGCAUCUAGUUUUGCCCCUGUCCUGCCCUUCCCUCAUCUAGAGUGAAGCCAGUAGGAACCUUCCAAAAUGAAAAUCUGAUUAAGUCACUUCUUUGCUUAAAACUUUUUUAUGGUUUCACAGCCCAUGAAAAUAGUAUCCAAUGUCUUUAAGUGCAUUGCAAAACUCUUCAAGGCCUCCCUCUCCAAUCCUUCUAGUCCUCCCUCCCCAGUUUCAUCACUCAUUAUAUACCCCAUAACCUUUAUGCCAGAGUUGUCAUGAACCUCCUCCCAUUCCUUCAGUAUUUUAUGUCUUUUUGCCUUCAGGUCUUUACACAUGUUGUUCCUUCAUAUUGAAAUAUUCUUUCCUCUCCCCAUUGCCUGGUAGAUUAACUCCUGUUUAUCCUUCAGAUGUCAGCCUUAAUGUCACUCUCUCAAGGUGAACAUCCCUGAAUUCUCUGAUGCAUUACAUAGGAUACCGUUUUUAUUCUGCCAUUGUAUGUG